AAGGUAGCGUGGCCGGCGCCCGAGCUGGGGUUGUGUCCCUGCUGGGCUGCCGUUCCAGCUGGACUGCCGCCAUGGAACUCAGCGCCGAAUACCUCCGCGAGAAGCUGCAGCGGGACCUGGAGGCGGAGCAUGUGGAGGUGGAGGACACGACCCUCAACCGUUGCUCCUGUAGCUUCCGAGUCCUGGUGGUGUCGGCCAAGUUCGAGGGGAAACCGCUGCUUCAGAGACACAGGCUGGUGAACGCGUGCCUAGCAGAAGAGCUCCCGCACAUCCAUGCCUUUGAACAGAAAACCCUGACCCCAGACCAGUGGGCACGUGAGCGACAGAAAUGAGGGACUGGGAUCUGCACAGCCAUUAAAUUAUAAAUCUGGACCA